GAUUUCCACUCUCUCUCCUGGCUGGCAGCGGGGAUCUGUGUCUCCAAGGAAAGUUUGCCCCGAGCCCUUCCCGGCCCGGCGUAGGGUUCUCCGGAAACCAUCACUCACAUCUAGCACUUGGAGGCCUCCAGGGACAGCGGUGACCCACCAUCUGGGUCUUGCCCCAGAAGCUGCGGGCACAUCCACGCCUGAAAUGCGGCGCUCAGUCCUGGUCAGGAACCCAGGCCACAAAGGCCUGAGACCCGUUUAUGAAGAGCUCGACUCUGACUCCGAGGACCUAGACCCCAAUCCUGAAGAUCUGGACCCGGUUUCUGAAGACCCAGAGCCUGAUCCUGAAGACCUCAACACUGUCCCGGAAGACGUGGACCCCAGCUAUGAAGAUCUGGAGCCCGUCUCGGAGGAUCUGGACCCCGACGCCGAAGCUCCGGGCUCGGAACCCCAAGAUCCCGACCCCAUGUCUUCGAGUUUCGACCUCGAUCCAGAUGUGAUUGGCCCCGUACCCCUGAUUCUCGAUCCUAACAGCGACACCCUCAGCCCCGGCGAUCCAAAAGUGGACCCCAUCUCCUCUGGCCUCACUGCCACCCCCCAGGUCUUGGCCACCAGCCCCGCGGUGCUCCCCGCCCCCGCCAGCCCGCCCCGGCCCUUCUCCUGCCCGGAUUGCGGGCGAGCCUUCCGCCGCAGCUCCGGGCUGAGCCAGCAUCGCCGCACGCACAGCGGCGAGAAGCCGUACCGCUGCCCCGACUGCGGGAAGUCCUUCAGCCACGGUGCCACCCUGGCUCAGCACCGUGGCAUCCACACUGGGGCGCGGCCGUACCAGUGCGCGGCCUGCGGCAAGGCCUUCGGCUGGCGCUCCACGCUGCUGAAACAUCGCAGCAGCCACAGCGGGGAGAAGCCGCACCACUGCCCGGUGUGUGGCAAGGCCUUCGGGCACGGCUCGCUCCUGGCACAGCACCUGCGCACGCACGGCGGCCCGCGGCCCCACAAGUGCCCGGUGUGCGCCAAGGGCUUCGGCCAGGGCUCUGCGCUGCUCAAACACCUGCGCACGCACACGGGCGAGCGGCCCUACCCGUGUCCGCAGUGCGGCAAGGCCUUCGGGCAGAGCUCGGCGCUGCUGCAGCACCAGCGCACACACACGGCCGAGCGCCCCUACCGCUGCCCCCACUGCGGCAAAGCCUUCGGGCAGAGCUCCAACUUGCAACACCACCUGCGCAUCCACACGGGCGAGCGGCCCUACGCCUGCCCGCACUGCUCCAAGGCCUUCGGCCAGAGCUCAGCGCUGCUCCAGCACCUGCACGUGCAUUCGGGCGAGCGUCCCUAUCGCUGUCAGCUCUGCGGGAAGGCCUUCGGCCAGGCCUCCAGCCUCACCAAGCACAAACGGGUGCAUGAGGGUGCAGCCGCUGCUGCAGCUGCCGCGGCCGCUGCAGCUGCAGCAGCGGCCGCCGGCCUGGGCCUCGGGCCUGGCCUAAGCCCUGCAUCCAUGAUGAGGCCGGGGCAGGUCUCCCUCCUGGGUCCUGAUGCUGUUUCUGUGCUCGGCUCUGGCUUGGGCCUCAGCCCUGGCACCAGCUCUGGCCGCAACCCUGACCCUGGCUCUGGGCCGGGCACUCUGCCGGAUCCCAGCUCCAAACCCCUCCCCGGCUCCAGAUCCACCCCCAGCCCUACUCCUGUGGAAUCUUCUGACCCAAAGGCUGGGCACGACGCUGGUCCCGACCUUGUGCCCAGCCCAGACCUUGAUCCUGUGCCCAGCCCAGACCCUGAUCCUGUGCCCAGCCCUGAUCCCAACCCUGUGUCCUGCCCUGACCCCUGUUCUCCCACUCGUGGCACUGUCAGCCCAGCCCUCCCUACCGGCGAGAGUCCAGAGUGGGUACAGGAGCAAGGGGCACUGCUGGGGCCUGAUGGCUGAAGGAGACGCCGGCAUCCUCGGGGGCCUGGGGAAGUUGUGUGUUGUGCAGUCAGUAAAAUCCUCCCACUGCCUCCGG